ACUCGGGAGCCUCGCGGCAGCCCGGCGCCCCACUUGGCCAUCCGCUCCUUGCCCGCCUCCUCUUGUCACCUCCCGUCUCAUCCUUCUCGCUCCUUCCCCGCCGCAUACACCGGCAUCCGAGUGCCUCAGAGAGCCGGAGGUGGUGUGCGGGGCUGCAGGGCACGACUUCAAGCGGUCCUCAGCUCCGCACUAGGGGGCACGGGCAACAGCAUGGACACCAAGCGCUGCUUCGCCAAUCGCUUCGAUGACUACCAGGGCAGCCUGCUGGCGGGCCAGUGUGAGGAGGCGGUGGCGCCCUUGGUCACCGCCACCAUCGAGCGCAUCCUCCAGGAGCUUCCCCCACUCGGGGGCGGCGCGGAGGCCCGAGGGGCGACGGCGGGGGCUAGCGCCUGCCAGGGGGGGCUUUAUGGCGGCGUGGCCGGAGUGGCGUAUAUGCUCUACCACGUCUCGCAGAGCCCGCUUUUCGCCACGGCCCGGGAACGCUACCUGCGCUCGGCUAAGCGCCUCAUCGACGCGUGCGCCCGCGCUGAGGAGUGGGGCGAACCGGACGCCGACACCCGCGCCGCCUUCCUGCUCGGGGGCGCGGGCGUGUACGCCGUGGCCACGCUCGUAUACCACGCCCUGGGCCGGUCCGACUACGUGCAGCCGCUGGGCAAGUUCCGGGCUCUGUGUGCCGUCUGCGCGCCGGUCUCCUUCCUGGAGUGCGGCUCCGACGAGCUGUUCGUGGGCCGCGCGGGUUACCUGUGUGCCGCGCUGGUGCUCAAGCAGAAACUCGCCCAGGAGGUGCUGACUCCAGCACAGAUCAAGUCAAUUUGUCAGGCAAUUCUGGACUCUGGGAAGCAGUAUGCCAUAAAGAAGAGGAAACCAUUCCCCCUGAUGUAUUCUUACUAUGGAACCGAAUACUUGGGGGCAGCUCACGGCUUGUCGUCUAUUCUUCAGAUGCUUCUUUCUUACCAUGAGCAUCUCAAGCCCUCAGAUCGGGAAUUGGUAUGGCAGAGCGUGGACUUUCUCAUGGAACAGGAACAAAACUGCAACUGGCCACCUGAGCUCGGCGAGACCAUCGAGAGAGAGAAUGAGCUGGUGCACUGGUGCCAUGGCGCUCCAGGAAUUGCCUAUCUGUUUGCCAAAGCUUAUCUGGUUUCCAAGAAACCGCAGUACCUGGACACAUGUAUUCGGUGUGGGGAACUCACAUGGCAGAAAGGCCUGCUAAAGAAGGGGCCUGGGAUUUGCCAUGGAGUAGCCGGCAGUGCCUAUGUCUUCCUGCUGCUGUACCGGCUCACGGGAAACUCUAAAUACAUCUACCGAGCUCAAAGUUCAUUCCCUGUAAACUUGAUAAAGAUGGAACAUCUGCUGUAUACCAGACAACAUUGCUUUUAAUAGAUAUUACCUCUGACUGGUUUGCUCAAUUCUUAUUUACCGAGGAAUUCAAGGCCGGUUCUCGGGUCCUUGAAAGUAUAUACAGCUUGUAUGAAGGCUUCUCUGGGACAGUGUGCUUUCUGAUUGACCUGCUGCAGCCCAAUCAGGCUGAAUUCCCACUCUUCAGCGUCUUUGUUUAGAAGGCUCUAUCUUCCACUGUGGCCCUGCAGAGAUCCCCUGAGCCAAGCCGAGGCAGUUUCCACAUAAGCCACAUUCAAUGGUAUCGCAACCAUGAGCCUUAACAUUGCCAUCAGAAGGAAGGAAUCAGGCAGGUGAAGGCAACAUGAUGCCAGAUUUGAGAAAGGAUCUGCAAAAUAAAGAUACCACAAUUCAUCUUAAAACUGCAGAGAUUUAAUGUGUCAGGGAAUAGAUGUGAAACAAGGGAUCAUAGGAAAAGGGGAAAGAGAAAUGAUCUGUUUUUCAGUUAUGACAUAGAAAACCAAACUGCAAGUGUAGACUAUGACAAAAAAUACACUAAUACCUUUGCAAUCUGAAUGAGAAUUUGACCAUUUGUGUGUGCCCUCUACCCUUAAAUUCAGAAAUAAAGACAAUAAAAAAUUAAAAUAAUUGCCCAGCUGAAAACUGCUAUGAGGAAUGGAUUGUCAGGUUGCUGAAGUAUAAAAAUAAACUCUUGGUUGUCCUGUGCUUAUACUUAUUGAAAUUUAUGGUUUUUACUGAGCAAAGAUAUUUGCAUAUGAAUCUCUAUUUUUUUCAUUACCCUGGGCAAUUUAAAGAAAUCAUAUCAUAGCGUAGUUCAGAUACUAAAAUUUGAAGUUUCCUUAGGCCCUAGAACAUCUCUUUUCCUGGUUCCUUUUUUUUCCUCAAAGCUCAAUUAGAAUAGCAAAAUUUAUAAGCUAGUAAACUUAUACUAUAGCAAGUGUUGCUGUAAAGUGUUUUUCUCCAUAGGAAGUGUGAACUGUGUAUUGUCUAUUGUUAGUAAUUUUAAAAAUGCCUUUAUGUACAUAAUCUUGAUGGAGCUAUUAGCUGAACUAUAAAAUAUGCUCUUGGUAAAUAUCACUAAUUUCAAAGAUCAGGGGAACCACUACAAAGACGUGUCAUUUCUGCCUUUGUUUGGGACAGGCAGACAGGCUGAGGAAGUCACCAGUGAUUGUGGAAAUAAUUUUGCUCCAUUUUAUACUAUUAAAUGAAGAGAUGAGUGAAUUCUGUGGUUGGUUACCUUACCUUCCAAGAUACAGGGUCCACUAGAAAUUGGCUGUAAUACUCAUUGAGCCAAGUUGUCAUAUCAAAUUCAACCCUGCUGUAAACACAUAGAAGUUGUGAAACUGCUUCAAGUAAAUAGUGGUUUGCAGAACACUGUAGGAGCAUCUGUCACUUCAUUAUGCAGAGCAUAAGUUGAUCCUUUUCCUAGAAUUUUGUCAGUGGCAAUUGCAUAUAUCAGAUUGAGUAGGAAAUUGUGUACUGUAUAAGACUUAUUUAAAUAGUCAUUAAAUAUUUGGAUAUAUUAUGUGUGUGUGUGUGUGUGUGUGUGUGUGUAUGGUGUGUAUUCCAUAUCUAUUCCCAUGUAAAUCCAAAUACUUAUUCUUUAUUUCAGUAAUUCUUAACUUGAAUCAUAGACUUUGGAACGAGUUAGGGAAUGCUCUGUUGCCUAAAAAGCAAACCUACAAGUAUGUUGGUGUGUGUAUGUGUAUGGACCAGUUUGUUUGUGUGUGUGUGUGCUCAUUUUGAGGGGACAAGGAUCUCUAGCAUUCAUAACAUUCUCAAAGAAUCUGACCAAAGAAAGGUAACAACUAUCUUUGUGUAUUUUAUGACUGUGUGUGUUUGCACUCAUUGCAAUAAAGUAGGACAAAAUGAUUUUGAAAUGCAUACAUCUUUUCAGCUUCCUGUUUCAUUUUUACAUCCUCAGAUACAACCAUAUCAAAUUGGCCUCAGUUGUUCAUCAGUGAAAAUGCUCAGUUUGGGGUGAUACCACAUAAAUAGCAGCUUUCAGAUGACUCCCCACAUUGGGUCCAGAAGUUCUUUCAUAUAGGCUGAAUAUAAUAACCAUCCUAUAUACAGAGCUUUAUGGAACACAUGCAGUUUUUAUCGUCCAAGAACCCCUCAAGAUGUGUUUGGUAAAUGCUCCAAAGUCUUACAGCUAGAAAAGGACAAAACCAGGAUUCAAACCCAGGGUUUCACUUUCUAAGUUUAUUUAUUCAGUAUUCUAGACUAGAAUCUGGGGAUACAAUAGUGAACAAAAUAAACUUUCCCUCAAAGCUACCUUCUGUUUCCAUUUGCUGUUCCUUUCACAAUUCAUCCUUGAGACCUGAAACCUAAAGCACUCAGAACUGAUACUCUAGUUCAUUAUCAUAUCAGUUCCAUUUCUAGUAACUUCAGAAAAACAAGACCACUUUCAGGCCUAUCUGCCCUUUUAAGUUCUGAUAGGUCUGAUGAUGAUGUGCUAACCAUUUUGAUUUGUGUGUCAAAUCUAAGCAAAGACCAUGUUUGAGUAUUGUCUUUAUGAAAUGACAUUUCGGUAAAUUAGAAACAACAAUAGGCUUGUUUAGCCCUUAAACAUGUUGAUGAAACUUUUCAUUUUCCUGAAAGAAUUAUAGAUUUUGGAAGGUCCUCUUCUAUAUUAUUUUUCCAAGAAGGGGAAAACGAUUCUUACAUUUUGCUGUAGGAAAGUGUGGCAUGUUACUUCUUAUUUAAUUAUCCAACUUGCCCCCCUUCUCUGUGGUAGCAUUUUUAAUGUAGUACUUAAGGCUGUUGUCUCUUAAAGGCUACAGGGGCAUUUUCACCACCACUAGUAUAACUUUAAUAUUAUUUACUAUAUACAGCAUGAGCAAUUAUAAACCCUGAAGGUAAUAGUGGAAAUGUUUGAGGAUACAUUGAAAUAGUCUCUCAAUAAUGGGGAGACUGCAUUAUGCUUUGAUAGCAAGACAUUUUGGAAACCAUUACAACUCUGUGUAUUUUGUUUCAUUAAUGUAAUUACAUACCAUCUCUUCCACACACACCCCAGAAUAUUAUACAUUUUUAUUUUGCCCAAGCCUGUUUCAGUCAUCAGUUUGUAGUCUUUUACUUCCACUUGUAACUUGAUAACUGAGUAGAACAGGGGUUUGCUAGAGUAUAUUUCCCUGUGCUUCUUUAGGUAGUUGACUAUGCUAUUAAGAUAACAGUAUUUGCUUACUGAUAACUUGAGAAACAGUCAUUUUCUUGGUCUGUGCUAAAUUGCAUCUCUUCCAGUGGCAGCUUAUUUCUUUAACUUUUUUGACAUAUUAAGAUUUUAAUCAUGGUAAUACUGAAAUUGUUUCAAAUUUGAAAGAGCGAACCUCAGUAACUUCAAUGAAACAAAUGGGUUUGUGAUUUCUAGCCAUGUUAAAUGAACACACAAUUAAAAGGAAAACCAUUAGUGGUGCAAAGAGCCCUGUGCUGGAAAUCUCAAAGUCUUGCUCUGCCACUUUUAGGGGCCACUGUAGUAAUAAUAAUAAUCACCCUGUCUACUUCACAGGGUUGUUAUAAAAGUUGUCAAUGAUAAAAUGGAUAUAAGUGAGUUUUUUAAUGUGCAGAUCCUUUAUAUAUUUAAAAGGGAUGUUAUAUUUUACCCACUAUAUACAUAGAAAAAUCAUGCCCAGUUAUGACUUCCAAUAAGAAUUUCAACCAAAUAGAAUCUCUAUAUGUGGAUGUAGUGCUUGAGGUCUGGGUCACUAGAUGGAUAAAAACCAAGUGUACAUUUUUUUAUAUUCUACCACCAGUCCUGAGCACAGCACUUUGCCUCAGAAGGUUCUGAUUCACCAAGACUUACUACAUGGGAAUAGACUGAUUUAGCUCAGGAGCUCCUUUUAAUGCAAAUAUUUAUUUUGCUUGCUGAGAACAAAGGAUUACAGUGCCAAUAACUCAAGAAAAGGAGCAGGCAAGCCAGGUCUGUAGAGAGAAAAUGAACUGGAAAAUAAAGUAAUUCUGGGGUGAGUUUGAUCUGCACUUUAAUUCAAGUCUCAGAACCACGUGACAUAUAGUGAUCAAAAUAUACUCUCAAUUGCAUAUUAGGCCUUCCUUUGGGGACCUGGGCUAUUUAUUCAGCACUGUCCCAAAUUAAUAGCUAAAUGACUGAGCCUCAAAUUUGCCGAGCCCGUGUAAUAUUGGUAUAAAUUUGGCAAGGAAAGCAAAUGAGAAGGCAGGCAAAGGGGUGGGUGAGGGGAAGCUUGCUGAAGCUCAGUAUCUCAAAGUGAGUUGUGGAUGCGUGUUUAACACUAUAAAGAACCAGUCCAUUCUUACCCAUGAGUUUUAUUGCUUUCUGGGACCUCUAACCCAGGACCACCCCUGAUUCACCAACUUCUCCUUCUUCUCCUCUUUAAAUAUUAUAGUUCAUUGUGAUAUGUUUUUCCUGUAUCUGCUCUAUCAUGUGACCUCCUUUCGCCUGGGAGGGCAGAUUUUCUCCUUAUCUCUUCCAUCCAUGUCUGUUCUUAGCUAAGAGUUCCAGCCUCAGUACAGCUGGAUUACCCUUUGGACAGAAGGGCAGACAACCUCAAGGUCAGCAGCAACAGAAGUUGGGCCUAGUAGUCAGAUCACAAGUGAGUGUGGCUAUUCAUGAGAAUAGGGUGGUGGUGGCAUUUAUCCUGCUUCCCCUCCAUAAAUAAACCUGGUAAUUUUAUUUUUAAUGUUACAAAAAAAGUUGAUGCUACAUUAAAUGUUUUACCCUCAUCCAUUAUCAUAAAUCUCAUACUGGAGGUGUGAUCUCUCUUCUUGUUUCUUUAAUUGAAAGUACCAAUGAAUCGAGGCCUGGUGGAUGAUGCCUUUAGAGUUUUUUGUUUUGUUUUGUUUUUGUUUUCUUGAAUCAUUGAAACUUGUCAUUUUUAUCUAGACUCUUCCACAAAUGGCAAAGUCACUUAUCUGCAGAAUUCCCAGAAUCUUCUUUUGCCUUUGUGCACCUGCUAAUUACCCCCUCUGAACUGAAUUUGAAAAAAUUAAUUAAAAUAACCGAAUCACCCAUGUUUUUGUUCUUGCAGGGUUUGGUGAGUUAUGUGGAUUAAAAGAACAGACUAUCCUCUCUCUUUUUUUGUCUUUCUUCUCCCUGUCCAAUACUGAGGAAGAAGAGGGAGAAGGGGGUAAAGAUACAUAAGGCUUAACUACCCAGGGUUAUGAAAACAGUUUGCAAAGUCUUCCUGUUUGCUUCCCUUUUGGUUUUUCUUAGUCCCUGUAGGAAAAAGUUUACCCCUCUGUGUGCGAGUGUGUGUGUGUGUGUGUGUAAGUAGUUGAGUGAAAAAGAAUGAGACUGACUUAAGGAGAGUCAAUAUCGCAUAUGAAUCAAAAGCCAACAUUUAGCUAUUAGAUAGAUCUCAGUGAAAGGAUAUGUUCAAGCUAAGUUGAUUAAGUUUAUUAAACUUAUUUAUUAAGCUUGACUAAGCUUAUUAAAACUUCUGCUAGGUUGAAGCCAUUAGUAACCAUCUGUAGAAGAUAACAGCCAUGAGUUUCACAAAUACAGCAGCAGUGUCUGCUAGAAUUGUGCUGUGAGCCACGAAUGCAAACCACAUAUGCAAUUUUCAAAUUUUCUAGUAGCUACCAAAAAGGUAAAAGAAAAAGAUGAAAUUAAUUUUAAUAAUGUAUUUGACUUAGCCUUAUAUAUCCAAAAUGAUAGCAUUUCAAUAUGCAAUCAAUAUAAAAACAUGAAUGAGCUAUUUUACAUUUUUGUACUGAGUCUUCAAACUCUAGUGUGUAUUUUAUACUUACUAUACAUCUCCAGUCUCGAAGUAGCCACAUUUCAAGUGUAUAAGAGCUGCAUGUGAGUUGGCUAUUGUAUUGGACAGUCCCAUUCCUGUUUCCUAGUAUUGAUAAAGUCUUCCUACCUUCCUUCGUUGUUAUGGGAGAAAAUGUAAACAGAACCUGCCUAUUACACGAGAGCUGCAAUAUUUCCCCAAAUGCAGCCCAGCAGUACCAUGAGCUGCCCUGUGGAAAAAUUUAAUCUGUGAUUAAAUAAGUUAGGAAAGUUUUAUUAUUUUACCCCCUUUUGAAGAUUACAUGGUACAUUAACAUAUUAAAGAUUGAGUAAACUCUCCUGGGUAAAAAAACCUGUUUGACGUUGUUUAGUUGUUGAGUUCUGUGUCUAUAAGAAUCCUAGAAAUUGCCACAAGUGUCUCUCCAUAAGAAAAACUUUGUGUUUUCCUCUCUUUCUCCACUCCUUUUGGGGCCCAUUUCUAUUUAUCUUUGUAUUCAGAAUCACCCGAGAGCCACAAUAUCUCUUUUGUUCUAGAACAACCACCUCCUAAAUUGAAACCAACAGAUGGCUUUAAAGUCUUGCACUUGGACAUAGAUCUUCAGAAAGUACCAAAAUAUAUACCUUCCUCUUAUUCUUUCAGAAACGGUGAACACUCUAAAAAGAUGUGGGGGUGUGGUGGGGGAUAUGUGAAUGUGUAUAUGUGUAAACACCAAAUACAUACAGUUUCUUAAGUAGAGUAAUGCAAUUCUUGCUGAUGUUUUAUUUUUAUUUUUAUUUUUUUAUUUUUUUUUUUUUUUGAGACGGAGUCUCGCUCUGUCGCCCAGGCUGGAGUGCAGUGGCGGGAUCUCGGCUCGCUGCAAGCUCCGCCUCCCGGGUUCACGCCAUUCUCCUGCCUCAGCCUCCCAAGUAGCUGGGACUACAGGCGCCCGCCACUACGCCCGGCUAAUUUUUUGUAUUUUUAGUAGAGACGGGGUUUCACCGUUUUAGCCGGGAUGGUCUCGAUCUCCUGACCUCGUGAUCCGCCCGCCUCGGCCUCCCAAUAUUUUUAUAUUUUGUGUGUGGUGACAAUGUACAUGCUUUAAUGUGUACUGUUCUAGUAAUAUGUAUGAAGUAGCUGUGACAUAGCAGUCAGUUUUAAAGAUACAGACUAUAAUUGACUACUGUCAAUCUUUAACAAGUGAUCUUUUUGCAACUUGGUUUUAGUGGGGUCUCUGACGUUGUCCCCACAAGUUUCAUUUUAAAAUCUAUGCUUAAGUGGCAGUUACCAAUAUAAUUAAUUCUGCUGCUGAAUUUGGUUCAUAUUGAAUGUGGUAACCCUUAUAUGUGGAUAUAUUCAAACAUGUGGAUUGAUUUAGAUCAUCCGUUUUGUCUUUGUUUUUUAGGACUUUGCUAUUUCAAUAUUAAAGAUGUCUUUUGAAUACUGUAGCAGCAGUAGAAUCCCUAUGUUCUUGAAAAUGCAAAAUGUAACAUGAGUUGCACAUAGACUCUCUAGCAGUAGAAAUGGAAUAUUCUAAGUGCAGAAGUUUGGUUUUAGAAUCUGUUAAGGAAGGACGGCCCAAUCUUUGAAAAGGUACAGCUUUCUCAACUUUGAACAUCUGGGGGAACUCUUCUUGGAAGUCUGAAUUUUAAUAUCUUUAAUCCAAUGGCUCUAAAUUAACAAACAUUAAAAAAUGGAUUUCGUAGAAUCAAAUUAUUAGGGGGAGCACUUUGCAAAGCCAUAUACUGGUGAAUAUAUACUGGGUCAAGCACCACAUGUUAGUUUUGGAAUGUGUAUUUCCCAGCGAAUAGAAUUUACUGCUCCAAAAAGCUUUUUUGGCAUAAAUCACAAUACUUACAGAAAUAUAAUUGUAUCAUUGAAAAAAACAAAGCUCACCUUCCUAAUGAUACAUUUCACAAACUGCACAUUAGGGCAAUUUCUUACUUAUGAGGAGGUACAAAGAAAUACUCUGUCAAUAUAGUAUAACUGCUUAUUUCAAAUUGUAUCUAGGAAUGAAUAACUACUAUUAUUUAAAGUACUACUGAAUUUUGAGGAACUGAUCAAAGAAUUAGUAUUAUUAAUAAAAUUGUACUAUUUGCAAUAUAUUUGCCUUGGCACAAAUGCAGAGUUAAAAACAUAAAAUUAUAAAAAAAAAUAAUAGUGAUUGGUUGUUACUACUUUAAAAUCCUACUAAUUUCCAUUAGCACUAAAUCAAACAGCACUUAUCUGUUGUAUACAAGUAAAAUUUUGAAAGACUCGGACACAAAAUGAAAGGCUUUUUAAAAAUGUCUUUGCCAUAACAGGUUAUAUGACCUCUUGCUAAUUGUUAUAUUUCCUUAGGGGCACUUUGAGGCUCUUUCAAAGACAUCUGCAGCAAUUAGGUCUAAAUUUAGAGUAGAAUAUUUUGCCAGAUAUUUUACUAUAUCACAAAAUGUCAUACUACUGUAUUUUAUAAUAAAACCAAAUUCUCAAGUAUUCUGGUAUGUUACAUAUUAAUAUACCAAAACAUCACUUUCUAUAAGUCUAUUAUUAUGUACAUAAUAUUUUUAAAAAUAAUGGGUAUUUUGGUCCUAGUGAAAAAGUAUAAUGCAAUACAUGACAUUAAUCUUUAGUCAAAACCCAUUGAGGUGUCUGACAGGGAAAUUAGCAAUCAUAAGCUAUAAGAUAUAUAUUAUUUUCAAGGACAAAAUGGCAAAUGAUAAUACAGAAAGACGUGAUCACUGGAGCAAGUUAGCUGGUGUGCAGACUAAGAAGGAUCAACUUGCAAAUGCUCAUCAGAAUUUAGCUUUUGUUAUUGGUUGUUCUGCAGGGGAUAGUACUAGUCAGUUGAUAUUGCUUCCCUUUCAUGUGGGAGUUUGCUCACAGCCCACUGCAUGGUAUAAUGAAAUCUCUAUAAGCAAGAUAGAGUCAGAAGCUUAGAGAUGCACUUUAUGGUUUUUACAACUGCUGUUACAAUGUUCUAAACACUGUGAUCUUUCCAAAUGUGUUUUCUGUAUUCGUUUUGUACUGUAGAAAAUAAUUCGCUAUAAACUGGACUUUAUAGUGUUUAAAGCGAUGUUAUUUAUUGGCUUAUUGCCCCUCCUUAUAAUACAUUUAUGUACAGUACACUUAAUGUAAAACCUGUGAUAAUCCUUUGCCUUAAAAUAAAAUCUAAUGCUAAAUA